UCCUCUGACCGAGCGAGGGCUCCCCGUCUGCGGCGCGGUCAGGACCCCGCACUUUCGGCCCGGCUCGGGGUUCUCGGAGUCCGUCCCAAGGCCGGGCCGCACCACCGCUGGGGGGCAGCGAAGCGAGCCUAGAGGAGAAAAGGCGGUCCCCGCCGAGUGCACGCCGGGGGCGGGGCACGGCACGAAGGCUCCGUGGUCGGACUUCUGGGCUGUUCGGAGGCCCUGGCCCACCUGGAGGGCCCUGGAAGAGUUUCCAGCGCUUCCCGAGGUAGGCGUGAGAAGCUCGACGCGGACCACAUCUCCCUCAUGCACCGCCCGCACGUCCCAGGAUGCGCUGCGAUUAAGGUACUGCCGCGCCUCGUGUGCAAGGACAGACUUCCGGGGUCGAGAACUACAACUUCCGACUUGCAUCACUGCGGUGGCGCUAAACAGCGUCAGCGAGGCGGUGCCCGACGAUUUCCCUGUCUUCCAGUUCCGCUCCCUGGGAUCAGCGGCGAGAAGCGGGGCGGAGUCUGAGGCCCGAGCCAAGAUGGCGGCUGCGAAGCCAACCCUCACGGACUCGCUCUCGUUCUGCCUCGCGCAGCUCGCGGCGGCGGCCGGGGAGGCUCUGGGUGGGGAAAAGGACCCAGCGACCAACGAGACACCCCUGAGCCGCGCGCUCCUAGCCCUCCGCACGCGCCACAUCAAGGCAGCGGGGGGAAUCGAGCGCUUCCGGGCACGCGGCGGGCUCCGCCCCCUACUCGCGCUGCUACGGCGAGCGGCUGCAGCGGGUUCCGCCCCGUCCCAGGCAGGCCCCGGCUCCGCCCCCUCGUCGGCCGCGUCGGGAGCUUCUAGCCCCGCCCCCGCGUCGGGCCCCGCCCCCUCCGCUGUGUCGUCGUCUAGUCCUACGCCGCCAGUGCGCCUGCGCAAGACGCUGGACUUGGCGCUCAGCAUCCUAGCCGAUUGCUGUACGGAAGGGGCGUGCCGGACCGAAGUGCGCAGACUCGGAGGCAUACUCCCUUUGGUGACCAUUCUUCAGUGCAUGAAGACAGACAGCAUCCAGAACCGAACGGCCCGUGCCCUGGGGAACUUAGCCAUGGAACCUGAGAGCUGUGGGGACAUCCACUGUGCUGGUGCUGUUCCCCUGCUUGUGGAGAGCCUGACAGCCUGCCAGGACUCGCAGUGCCUACAGAGCGUGGUGCGUGCCCUCCGUAACCUGGCAGACUCACCCCAGCACCGCCUGGCCUUGGCACAGCAGGGAGCAGUGCGUCCGCUGGCCGAGCUCCUGGCCACUGCCCCAGAUGCUGCACUGACCUUAGCCCUCGUCCGUGCCCUCCUGGAACUCAGCCGAGGCUGCUCCCGGGCCUGUGCUGAGCAGCUAAGUCUGGGUGGGGGAUUGGGCCCACUCGUCAGCCUGGCUUCCCACCCCAAGCGGGCAGUACGCGAGGGAACCAUUCUGAUCCUCGCCAACCUGUGUGCCCAGGGCCUGAUUCGGCCUGCACUGGGCAAUGCUGGUGGCGUGGAGGUGCUGGUAGAUGAGCUCCGGCAGCGCCGGGAUCCUAAUGGAGCUAGCCCAACCUCCCAGCAGCCCCUGGUGCGGGCUGUGUGCCUCCUAUGUCGUGAGGCCAUCAACCGGGCCCGACUGCGGGAUGCUGGUGGCUUGGAUCUACUGAUGGGCCUGCUGCGGGACCCUCGUGCAAGCGCAUGGCACCCUCGUAUUGUGGCUGCCCUUGUGGGGUUUCUGUAUGACACUGGGGCCCUGGGCCGGCUGCAGGCUCUGGGACUUGUGCCUCUCCUGGCUGGGCAGCUGUGUGGUGAGGCUGGUGAGGAGGAAGAAGAGGGAAGAGAAGCUGCUUCCUGGGACUUUCCUGAGGAGAGGACCCCUGAGCGGGCACAGGGUGGAAGCUUCCGGAGCCUCAGGUCGUGGCUGAUCUCCGAGGGCUAUGCCACAGGCCCUGAUGACAUCUCCCCCGACUGGUCUCCUGAGCAGUGUCCGCCGGAGCCCAUGGAGCCGGCCAGCCCCGCCCCGACCCCGACCUCGCUGCGGGCACCACGCACCCAACGCACUCCGGGCCGCAGCCCCGCCGCCGCCAUCGAGGAGCCUUGGGGACGCGAAGGGCCAGCCCUGCUGCUGCUGUCGCGCUUUUCCCAGGCCCCUGACCCAAGUGGGGCACUUGUGACCGGCCCGGCGCUGUACGGCCUGCUGACCUAUGUGACCGGCGCACCGGGCCCGCCCAGCCCACGUGCACUGCGCAUUCUGUCACGCCUCACCUGCAACCCUGCCUGCCUCGAGGCCUUCGUGCGCAGCUAUGGCGCGGCGCUGCUGCGGGCCUGGCUGGUGCUGGGGGUGGCGCCUGACGAUUGGCCGGCACCACGUGCCCGGCCCACUCUCCACAGCCGGCACCGAGAGCUGGGUGAGUUCCCAUACCCACCCGUCUCCUUGCCCCCAUGUGAGUCCCCAUCCUCCCCCAUGGCUUCCAUGGGCCCAGAACCUCACCUUCCCACUCACCUGUCCUCCCCAGCCCGUCCUCCAGACAACCUGUCACCAGAGUGGGGUGGGGAGCAGGGCGUUCCAGUCCCUCCAUGGGCCCACAGGCAGAGUUCUGCUGUGUCCUCUGCCCUAGCCCUGGGACCCAGAUACCCUAACUCUAGAUGCAGCCCCGCGCCCAGGAUCUGGGCUGGUCUGUGCUUCUUUCCUGGCUCUGCCAUUGGUUCAGCACUGUCCUGACUGCUCCCCACCAGCACGCUGACCUGUGAACCCCAGCCUCACCAUCACCCCCAGCACUGCCAGGGACUGCCCUGUCUGCUGUGCCCUGACCACAGGCUGCUUCAUGGCGUUACUGCUAGACCAAGGAGCCCUUCUGCUGGCCCUGUCCGGGCAUAACAGAAGGCUCGCACUCUUGUCUUCUGGUCACACCUCACUAUGUCCCCUCAGCUCCUAUCUCUGUAUGGCCUGGUUUUUCCCAGGUUAUGAUUAUAGAGCGAGGAUUAUUACAAUAUUGGGAUAAAGAGUAAUUACUACAAACUAAUGAUUAAUGAUAUUCAUAUAUCUCUAAGAUCUAUAUCUGGUAUAACUAUUCUUGUUUUAUAUUGUAUUAUACUGGAACAGCUCGUGUCCUCCGUCUCUUGCCUCGGCGCCUGGGUGGCUUGCCGCCCACACUUCAGGGGCCCAGACUUACACCCUGACUGUCCCACCUUCUGUCCUUGUCCUGGACCUCAGGUUCCCAGCGUCCCGAGCCCAGCACUGUCUCUUCAGUGCCCUGAUUUCUCACCCAGAGGUUUCACCCUCCUUCAUCUCACGGGCCCAGAGCCCUGUCUCACUCACCCCACCUGUCUUAGACCCCAGUUCCCAGCCUGACAAGCUUUCCACUCACAGGGGAGAGGCUACUGCAGAACCUGACGGUUCAGGCUGAGUCGCCCUUUGGGGUUGGGGCCCUGACGCACCUGCUGCUCUCUGGGAGCCCUGAGGACCGAGUGGCCUGCGCGCUGACCCUGCCCUUCAUCUGCCGGUGAGUGGGAAGUGGGUGCCUUGCGGGGUUGGGGGAGGAGUGCUGUGUUUCCCAGGCCCGUUGCCCACCUUUUGAAAGGCCCUCUCUUCCCUGUAGGAAGCCCUCUCUGUGGCGCCGGCUGCUUCUGGAGCAGGGUGGUCUCCGGCUCCUCCUUGCGGCGCUGACCCGGCCGGCCCCACACCCGCUCUUCCUCUUCUUUGCCGCGGACUCCCUUUCCUGCCUCCAAGACCUGGUGUCUCCCACUGUGAGCCCAGCUGUCCCACAGGCAGUCCCCAUGGACCUAGACUCACCUUCCCCUUGCCUCUAUGAACCUCUGCUGGGCCCAGCCCCUGUCCCAGCUCCCGACCUGCACUUCCUGCUGGACUCAGGCCUCCAGCUCCCUGCCCAGCGAGCGGCCUCAGCCACCGCCUCCCCUUUCUUCCGGGCCCUGCUGUCAGGCAGCUUUGCAGAAGCCCAGAUGGACCUGGUGCCCCUGCGAGGUCUGUCGCCUGGUGCAGCCUGGCCUGUCCUGCAUCAUUUGCAUGGUUGUCGGGGGUGUGGGGCUGCCCUGGGGCCCGUGCCCCCACCAGGCCAGCCCCUGCUGGGUUCAGAGGCCGAGGAGGCACUGGAGGCUGCUGGCCGUUUCCUACUGCCUGGGCUGGAGGAGGAGCUGGAAGAGGCCGUGGGCCGCAUCCACCUGGGACCCCAGGGUGGCCCGGAGUCAGUGGGUGAGGUGUUCCGCCUGGGCCGGCCCCGGCUGGCUGCCCACUGUGCCCGCUGGACACUGGGGUCAGAGCAGUGCCCGAGGAAGCGGGGUCUGGCCCUGGUGGGGCUUGUGGAGGCAGCAGGUGAAGAGGCAGGGCCCCUGACGGAGGCUUUGCUGGCUGUGGUGAUGGGGAUUGAGUUGGGGGCAAGGGUCCCUGCCUAGACUGUUGACGUCCCCUGGGAAGGGGACCCAAGGAUGAAUUGGCUGUGAAGGAUCCUCCCUGAGACUGGCAAGGGAGGAGGCUGAGCAGAAGGAGUCAUCAUGGAGGAGCGGUGAGAACAUGGAACCGGACUCCAAGAUGACGAUCUAAAGACCCGGGAGCGAGAAGCCAAGGCCAGGUUCUGGGUGUAGGGCCCAGAGAAGCAGAACAGCCCAGAGCCCCAGGUGCCUGGCCUGGCCUAGACCUCUGGAAUUGAGAUUAAACAAUUUGGAGUUGGAUA